AGUCCCGCCUAGCGCGCCCAUUUCGAGCCCAAGUUUCCAGCUCGGGUUUCCAGGCUCAGAAUUUUCCAGGAGUAGGUUCUUGGGCAGUGGCUGUGGGAGCUGGAAUGGCGCAGCUGGAAGGUUACUAUUUCUCGGCCGCCUUGAGCUGUACCUUUUUAGUAUCCUGCCUCCUCUUCUCCGCCUUCAGCCGGGCGUUGCGAGAGCCCUACAUGGACGAGAUCUUCCACCUGCCUCAGGCGCAGCGCUACUGUGAGGGCCAUUUCUCCCUUUCCCAGUGGGAUCCCAUGAUUACUACAUUACCUGGCUUGUACCUGGUGUCAAUUGGAGUGAUCAAACCUGCCAUUUGGAUCUUUGGAUGGUCUGAACAUGUUGUCUGCUCCAUUGGGAUGCUCAGAUUUGUUAAUCUUCUCUUCAGUGUUGGCAACUUCUAUUUACUAUAUUUGCUUUUCUGCAAGGUACAACCCAGAAACAAGGCUGCCUCAAGUAUCCAGAGAGUCUUGUCAACAUUAACACUAGCAGUAUUUCCAACACUUUAUUUUUUUAACUUCCUUUAUUAUACAGAAGCAGGAUCUAUGUUUUUUACUCUUUUUGCGUAUUUGAUGUGUCUUUAUGGAAAUCAUAAAACUUCAGCCUUCCUUGGAUUUUGUGGCUUCAUGUUUCGGCAAACAAAUAUCAUCUGGGCUGUCUUCUGUGCAGGAAAUGUCAUUGCACAAAAGUUAACGGAGGCUUGGAAAACUGAGCUACAAAAGAAGGAAGACAGACUUCCACCUAUUAAAGGACCAUUUGCAGAAUUCAGAAAAAUUCUUCAGUUUCUUUUGGCUUAUUCCAUGUCCUUUAAAAACUUGAGUAUGCUUUUGCUUCUGACUUGGCCCUACAUCCUUCUGGGAUUUCUGUUUUGUGCUUUUGUAGUAGUUAAUGGUGGAAUUGUUAUUGGCGAUCGGAGUAGUCAUGAAGCCUGUCUUCAUUUUCCUCAACUAUUCUACUUUUUUUCAUUUACUCUCUUUUUUUCCUUUCCUCAUCUCCUGUCUCCUAGCAAAAUUAAGACUUUUCUUUCCUUAGUUUGGAAACGUAGAAUUCUGUUUUUUGUGGUUACCUUAGUCUCUGUGUUUUUAGUUUGGAAAUUCACUUAUGCUCAUAAAUACUUGCUAGCAGACAAUAGACAUUAUACUUUCUAUGUGUGGAAAAGAGUUUUUCAAAGAUAUGAAACUGUAAAAUAUUUGUUAGUUCCAGCCUAUAUAUUUGCUGGUUGGAGUAUAGCUGACUCAUUGAAAUCAAAGUCAAUUUUUUGGAAUUUAAUGUUUUUCAUAUGCUUGUUCACUGUUAUAGUUCCUCAGAAACUGCUGGAAUUUCGUUACUUCAUUUUACCUUAUGUCAUUUAUAGGCUUAACAUACCUCUGCCUCCCACAUCCAGACUCAUUUGUGAACUGAGCUGCUAUGCAGUUGUUAAUUUCAUAACUUUUUUCAUCUUUCUGAACAAGACUUUUCAGUGGCCAAAUAGUCAGGACAUUCAAAGGUUUAUGUGGUAAUAUCAGUGAUAUUUCGAACUGUGAAAAUGGACUUAAUAAUUAGACCAUUUCUACAAAGAACAACUGAAUAGGUGGAAAACAUGGAAUUUCUUUUAGGUGCAGUGGUGGUCUUCAAAUUACAUUAGUUUUUUUUAUAUAUAUUUUAAACAUAUGUAAGAAAUUAAGUGGCAAAGAACUGAGAAAGCUUAAGACCUGCUUCAAAAGCCUGAAAAAUGGAAAAAUAAAAUUGUUUUCAGAUAUCUCAUAUCACUCUCAUAAUGUUGGCCCCUUAAAAAGCUUGGGAAUGUUUUGUAUGUACAAGUUUAUUAAAACUGGGUAUGCUUCAUAUUACUGGAAUGAAUUUAUUCUCUUCAGAGAGAAAUAUUAGGUUAGUGCAAAAGUAAUUGUGGUUUUUGCCAUUGAAAGUAAUGGCAAAACCACAAUUACUUUUUUACCAACCUAAUAACAAUGUAUUAGCAAAUAUUUACAAAUGGUCAGGUGAUAUUCUUGAUUGAAAAGUUGCUUAACAUUUCAGUAAUAUAAUUUUAAUUCUAAGUCAAAAUACAAAUGCAUAGAUAGUAAAUGAUAAAGUAGAGACUCAUAUAUGCCUGUCUAGACAUCAAAUUGUUGGUUAUUGUUUACAAUCUAGAAAUGAUGAAGCUCUUUCACUAAUUCCUAAUAUGAAAUGUAUGAUGGCCAAAGACAAAUUGUAUUGAUUAUAAUCCUUUAAAAGGGGGAUUUCCUUUCUGAAAUACAUAUUGUAUUAGCUUCCCAGGGCUUCCAUAACAAAUGACGACAAACUUGGGUGCUUACAACAAUUUUCCUCACAGUCUGGAGGCCAGAAGUCUAAAAUCAAAGUGUCAGCAGAGUUGGUUCCUUCUGGAGGCUCUAAGGAAGAAUCCAUAAACAGACAUUCUAUGUCUGUUUCCUAAUAUCUUGUGGCUGUGUGCAAUUCUUGGAGUUCUUUGGCUUCUGGACAAAUCUUGUCCAAGUAUUGCAGACAGCAAUCUUCACUCCAGUCUCUGCCUCUGUGUUCACACGGCCUUUCCCUCUGUCUUCUCUUCAUUACCUUUUAAGGACAGUGUCUUUGAAUGUAGGGCCCACCCUGAUCUAGGGUGAUUGUGUCUGGAGACCCUUAAUUAUGUUUACAAAGACCCAUGUUCCAAGUAAGUUUGUAUUCACAUGAUCUGAGUAGACAUUGUCUCUUCGUGGGAUACUUUUCAGUCCAUGACAGUUACUAAAGGACAUUUUAGGAUAGUCUUCAUAUGAUUGUUAGGAGACUACCUUUUUAGAUUUUUUUUAUUAUAUAUCAAAUUAUAGUUGUAUAUACUUAUGAGAAACAAAGUGGCAUUAUGAUUUUUGAAUAUAAUGUGGGAUUAAAUAAAGCUAAUCUAUCCAUCACCUCAAA